AGGUGUCUGUCUUCUGGAGCACCAGGGGACCUCAGCACUGAGGAAGAAGCGUGUGCCUGGCCCUUGAUUUCAGUUGGUAGUAUUCUUUCAGCGCAGGGCCCUGUAUUUUAAAGAAGAGGAAGCUAUGUCUGUGAUAUAGACUCCAUGCCUAGUAAGAAGAGCCAACAAAUCUGACUCCGUAAUUCUUGCUAAGUAAAGAAACCUGAGCUGUCUAAGCUGAAUGUAUCUGUGACCCGGUUGACUAGGUAAUAUGCCAUGAUUCACUUCUGCAGUAGCCUGGCUUGCCUCCCCUGGGUCACUGUGACUCUGUCAUGCCCCUGAGCAUGGGAGAGGUUGACAUCAUGCACACAUGCACAUGUGCUAGAUUGUAGAUCUGUAGUAGUGCCACGGUGUCUGCCUCUGUAGUCCCAAGAAGACCAGCAUUCUCUCUGCAAAGUGAAAGGAGCUCUCACCAGCCACUAGUGGUAUGAAAAGCAGAACUCUUUUGUCCACAAGGCUGAUGCCCCUUAGCUAAGUGGCCUGUGGUUUUGGCAUUUACUUUAUGACAGGAGGGAGAAUAGUGUUUUGAUCCAUUUCUUAUAAGCAGGUUAUUUGUAUAAUUCUAAAGCUUUUAACUCAAGGAAACAUUAACGGCUUAGAGAAUCCCAAACCCCUCGAAAUUAUAUGCACAAUGUUAGAGACUACAUGUGAGCAUUUUUUUGGAGAGAGGUCCGUAGCUUUCAUGAAGUUCUUAGAGGGGUCCAUUAUGUUGUGUCUUCUUUCCCUGGAGCUUCAGGGUCUGUCAGAGAAGACUGUGAAGAGAGUAGCAGCCUUCAGCAAGUCCUUGGCCACAUGACACAUGUGAGAACACCCCACAAAUCGGUGGGUUAGCCGGUGGAAAGGAGUCCCAGCAUCUUCCCUGGUUUUUAAUUCCUGGCCUCAAGCAAUCCUCCCUCCAUAACCUCCCAAAGUGCUGGGAUUACAGGCGUGAGACACCAUGCGCAGCCAGAUAUUUUUUAUUGUUGUUGUUUUUUUUUGGAAAAGGAGUUUCACUCUUGUUACCCAGGCUGGAGUGCAAUGGCACGAUCUCGGCUCACUGCAACCUCUGCCUCGCAGGUUCAAGAGAUUCUCCUGUCUCAGCCUCCCGAGUUGCUGGGAUUACAGGCAUGCACCACCAUGCCCAGCUAAUUUUGUAUUUUUAAUAGAGACAAGGUUUCUCCAUGUUGGUCAGGCUGGUCUCAAACUCCCGACCUCAGGUGAUCCACCCACCUCGGCCUCCCAAAGUGCUGGGAUUACAGGCGCGAGCCACUGCACCUGCCCAGCCAGAUUUUUUUUUAAAAAGCAGGUUAACCUGUUUAUUAUUCCUACUUUACAGAUGGAGAAAGUGAGACAGAGGGAUUAAAUAACUUGCCCAGGGUUUCACAGCUGGCAAGUGGCAGAGUUAGGAUUUGGACCCAGGUAGUCUUGCUCCUCUAUUGUGUAUGGACUACUGUUCUAGGUCCCUGCUGUCCUAAAACUUGCUUUCUAGCAAGGUGGAAUGUAUUAAACAACCAAGUGAGGAAGUCGUUGUUGUCCUUGGCCAUGGUAAGAGAUACAGAGAAGUGCAGGGUGCCACAGGAGUGUCUAACAGAGGAGGUCAGGGGCAGCAUCCCUGAGAAGGUGAAGCAUGAGCGAGAGUGGGAAGAUGAGUCGAAAGUAGCCAGCUGAGGGGUAGAGAGGAGAAAGAACAUCCAGGCAGGGAGAAUAGCAAGUGCUAAAGCCGGGGCUCAUGAAAAGGCAUGGGAGCAGGACAAAGUCCGUGUGGUAGAGGUGCGGAGAGUGGUGUUAAGAUGAAGGGGAGAGGCAGGCAGAGCCCUGGGCAGAUGAGCAACCAGGGCUUAGUGGAUCACAGUUAGGACUUUGGGCUUCAGCCACAGAGCAGCGGUGGGCUACUGAGAUUUUUUAAAGCAAUAGUGUGACAAUCAGAUUUGUCCUUUUUUUUUUUUAAAGAUGCUUUGACAACCUUGUGAAGAAAGAAUUGAAGGGAAGCAAAAGGUGUUGUAGAGAGACCAAUUAAAAGGUUGUCACAGUAGUUCAUGCCAGAGAUGAUGGUGGCAUGGCCUAGCAUGACGGUGGUAGAAAUGGAGGGAAGUGGUAAGAGGUAAAAUCAACAAGACUUGCCGAUGGGCUGGAUGUCGGAAUUGGGGGAAGAAAGCUUUCUGGCCUGAGUAACUGGGUGAAUGAAGGUACACUUCUCUAAGACAGAGAAUGCUGGAAAAGAACCACGUUCAUGGAUAUUGAGUUCAAUUUGUGUGUACUAAAUUUGGGGUGACUAUGAGACCCCUAAGUGGAGAAGUAGAGUGUGAAGCUGGCUGUAUGGAUAUGGUACUGCAUGAGAGGUUUUGGCUAGAGAAACACAUGUAGGAUUUGUCAGCAUAUAGAACCCUCAGCAGAGCCCCAGAUAGGGAUGAGGUUGCCUGGGGAGAGGGGAGUGGGGAGGGGAGGGGGGAACUGGGGGAGGAUUGUGCUAUGCUUAGAGGCCACCUGAGUGGACAUGGGAGAUUCCUUCUCACGGAGCUAAGUGACAGCUGCGGCUCAGAAGAAUGCCCUUGAUGUGAAAAGGAGAUACCCCAAGUUCAGAGUAGAAAUGCAGUGUAUUUUUCUGGGUCAGCUGUGUCAUGGGUCAGCUUAAGAACCUUCUUGCCAUGUGACACAAUGAUUACCUGAGGAAAGCAUUUAAGUUCCAAAAGGUCUAUUCCCAGGGAAACUGGAAACAAAAUUUGUGAGUGUGUUUAGGACCACUUUAGUCUACAGAAGGGCUAAUAUAGUGUUUUUCAAACCUUUCUAAACAUUUUGGCCACAGAACUUUCAUUAAAGUAGGAUAAUUUAAGUCUAGUAAAUGAAAUACACCCUAAGUGGCUAAAAGUAUGGCUGUUCUGCCUGCAGCCCCUGCCUUCAAUUCCCAAUGCCCUGCCUCAAGCCUGUCUGUGCCCCCUUGGAAGGCCCAGGGCCCUGUGGGAUGGACAGCUUCUGAGUGCAUUACUUCUGAGUAAACCAGUUCUAAAACCUAAGCUAAGUAGAUUACCUGAAAGCAAUCAAUUCAUGCCCUAACUUGUCUAGGACAUCAAUGUAACUUUUUAUAUAGUAUAAAGGUUUCACCUUCUUUCUGGCCUAUGAAUAUGUCUGAAAUUCAAGAGCAAUUAAAGUACUCCUGGGUUGUCAAAGCCCUUUAUGUAACACUAUUGAGUUAUCUUUAUGCGUCUGACUUGUAAGAGAUGCACAACUCUAGGAAGAAGUAGACUGCUGUGUCCUGUUUCCAGGUAUGUGUGUGUUUGCCAUUUUGUUGACAGACUUUAAAAGCAAACAUUUCUGGCCCCAACCCUGAACUGCCAAGGACUGGUGCUAUGUAAAGGGUUCUCUGGAUCUGUCUCUUCCCUACCAUCCCAGGGAGCUCUUAGGAAGGGAAAGGGCAUAGAGAUUAUACCAGCCUGCCUUGUGGUUAGGAACCACCCCUUGGUUGGCAUAUAGAACAUGCUUGUUAAAAAAACCAUGCAGGGGAAAGUAGAGUCUACUACCAGGCGAGAGUUUCUCAACCUCGACCCUAUUAACAUUUUGAGCCAAAUAAUUUUGUUCUAGGGCAUUUUCCUGGGCAUUUUAGAAUAUUUAACAACAUAUCUGGCCUCUACUCAUUAGAUGCCAGUGAACCCCAAGUGAUGGAAAAAAACAACAACAACAGAAAAAAACCUCUUUUAUUGAGGAAAAACACCAAACUCUUCCACAUAGUUGCAAGACCUUGUGCAAUUUGCCUCCUAGCCACCACUGUACUCUUGAAUUGCACGCCUGAUGCCAACCACACUGGUUCCUCAUGUUCACCAUGCCCCCUCCAGCCAUGGGGGUGUGUGGUCUUCUCAGAGUCUGAAGCAUUCCCCACCCACCCCAACCCACCCCCUGUGGCCUUCUUUAACCAUGCUGGCUAAUUCAGGAUCCCUAGUUCCUUAUGACUUUCCUUUAAAACGUCUACCAGAAAUUGGGGGAAAAAAAGUGUUAUUAUAGGAUUAAUGUUGGUCUUCCGCACUAUACUGUGAAUAUCAUUGAGAGCUUGGUCCCUACACCUUAAAUCCCCCAUCGUCAACUAUUUUUUCCCAUCUCAGUGUCCCAUGAUCAAGGAGACCCUCCCUGAAUGUCCAGUUCCCCAACCCUUACCCCCAGUCCAGGGUAGCUUCCUUCCUUGUGCCUCUCAUUAACCUGCAUGCCGAUCCUUCAGUGCACUUGACUCAGUGUGUAAUUGUAUAUUCAGUAGCGUGUUGUUAGAUUAAAAUGUGGUUAAUAUGUGUUUCACCAGUUAUACUAUGACACUCCUUAAGGGCAGAAACAGCAUCUUUUUUAAUUUAUUGAUAUCCAAGUGCCCUCUAUAAUAGAUGCUCAAUAAACAUUGAAUGAAAGUGGGUGUCAGCCAGUACUGGCCAGACUCAAACUGAACCCACUGCUUCCCACUAGCUUGACUUUUUCCUCCUGUUUGUGGCACUCUCUUUAAAACAAACCAAAAUAAACCCAAUUUUAAAAACUUUUUAAAAUGAGCACGGAUACAGAAAACCACACAGAACAAAUGUGUAGCUUAAUGAAUUUUUUUCAGAGAAAUAACCUUAUGACCACCACCAAGUCGAGCAGUAGAACUUUGCUGUCCACUAAGAAGCCCUGUCCAUGUGCCCCAUCCCAAUUACAGCAUCCUCUCUCUCUCCCCAUUAAGUAACCGCUAGCCUGACUCCUGUAAUAAUCACUUCCUUGUGAGUUUUUUUAGUUUUAUUAUCGAAAUAUGCAUCCUUGACACAAAUUUAGUGUUGCCCACUUAAUAUAUUUGAUGUCUUUUAGUCUACUUAAUCUAUGGAUUCUCCUUCUAUCGCCUUCUAUGCCUUACUGAUUAUCUAUGAAGAACCUGAGCUAUUCCACCUAUAGAAUUUCCCAGUCUGGAUUUGUUGAUUGCACACUGAUGAUGCAGUUCAGCACAUUCCUCUAUGCUCUGCAUUUCCUCAAAAUUGGCAGUUGGAUCCAGAGACUUGAGAUUCAGGUUCUGAUUCAGGUUCAGUCCUUUUGGCCAGACCAUAGGAAGCAUGCAAUUCCUGACUGUCUCUUUAUGAUGUUAACAGUAAUUAGUAUAUAAUGCAUAGAUCUAUUAAUCCAUUGGGGGCUAUAAAUGGUAUUAUUCUAAUUUUAUUACCUUUUCAUUUAAAAGUUAGAAUACUUUUGUACAUGAUACUACCUCUUAUCUAUUAUUGGUUGCUGUUCACAUAGUUUACAAAGGAAAAUCAGGACAAAUGUUUCUUUCUCUUUAUUUGCCAGUUUUCAUUUAUAAUGAAUUGUUUCUCUGUUAUUCUCCAAAUUUGGCAGAUUCUUUUUUAAAAAAAAUAUCAUUAUGAAUGUAUGGAUUAAAUAAUUGAUGUAUUUCAGUCUCUUGCAAUCAUUAUCAUAAUUGUAGCAUUGCUUUUUAGGCAACCCUGGUACCCAGGCUGUACAUUUGUCAUGGGGAGUGGGGAGGGGGAGAAAUAGCAUGGGCACUGUGAGACCGAGACUGUCCCUGGCAGCCAGUAUUCUGGCAACACUGUUCACACCCACUUACUGGAUGGAUCUUGAGAAAGCCCCACUUGGUGGAGCCCAUUCCUGCUGCCCUUUUCCAGCUGGUUAUCUGUCACUCUCCUUUUCUUCCCAGGUUUGGCCGGAAGAAUGUGCUGUUCGUGACCAUGGGCAUGCAGACAGGCUUCAGCUUCCUGCAGAUCUUCUCGAAGAAUUUUGAGAUGUUUGUCGUGCUGUUUGUCCUUGUAGGCAUGGGCCAGAUCUCCAACUAUGUGGCAGCAUUUGUCCUGGGUAUGGCCAUCAGGUUGGAGGACAGAAAUUCUUGGCAAGUCAGUUCGUAUAAUAUUCUCUACGUUAGGAGUGUGCAUAUUUUAUGCAUUUGGCUACAUGGUGCUGCCACUGUUUGCUUACUUCAUCCGAGACUGGCGGAUGCUGCUGGUGGCGCUGACGAUGCCGGGGGUGCUAUGCGUGGCACUCUGGUGGUUCAUCCCUGAGUCCCCCCGAUGGCUCAUCUCUCAGGGACGAUUUGAAGAGGCAGAGGUGAUCAUCCGCAAGGCUGCCAAAGCCAAUGGGAUUGUUGUGCCUUCCACUAUCUUUGACCCGAGUGAGUUACAAGACCUAAGUUCCAAGAAGCAGCAGUCCCACAACAUUCUGGAUCUGCUUCGAACCUGGAAUAUCCGGAUGGUCACCAUCAUGUCCAUAAUGCUGUGGAUGACCAUAUCAGUGGGCUAUUUUGGGCUUUCGCUUGAUACUCCUAACUUGCAUGGGGACAUCUUUGUGAACUGCUUCCUUUCAGCGAUGGUUGAAGUCCCAGCAUAUGUGUUGGCCUGGCUGCUGCUGCAAUAUUUGCCCCGGCGCUAUUCCAUGGCCACUGCCCUCUUCCUGGGUGGCAGUGUCCUUCUCUUCAUGCAGCUGGUACCCCCAGACUUGUAUUAUUUGGCUACAGUCCUGGUGAUGGUGGGCAAGUUUGGAGUCACGGCUGCCUUUUCCAUGGUCUACGUGUACACAGCCGAGCUGUAUCCCACAGUGGUGAGAAACAUGGGUGUGGGAGUCAGCUCCACAGCAUCCCGCCUGGGCAGCAUCCUGUCUCCCUACUUCGUUUACCUUGGUGCCUACGACCGCUUCCUGCCCUACAUUCUCAUGGGAAGUCUGACCAUCCUGACAGCCAUCCUCACCUUGUUUCUCCCAGAGAGCUUCGGUACCCCACUCCCAGACACCAUUGACCAGAUGCUAAGAGUCAAAGGAAUGAAACACAGAAAAACUCCAAGUCACACAAGGAUGUUAAAAGAUGGUCAAGAAAGGCCCACAAUCCUUAAAAGCACAGCCUUCUAACAUCGCUUCCAGUAAGGGAGAAACUGAAGAGGAAAGACUGUCUUGCCAGAAAUGGCCAGCUUGUGCAGACUCCGAGUCCUUCAGUGACAAAAGGCCUUUGCUGUUUGUCCUCUUGACCUGUGUCUGACUUGCUCCUGGAUGGGCACCCACACUCAGAGGCUACAUAUGGCCCUAGAGCACCACCUUCCUCUAGGGACACUGGGGCUACCUACAGACAACUUCAUCUAAGUCCUAACUAUUACAAUGAUGGACUCAGCACCUCCAAAGCAGUUAAUUUUUCACUAGAACCAGUGAGAUCUGGAGGAAUGUGAGAAGCAUAUGCUAAAUGUACAUUUUAAUUUUAGACUACUUGAAAAGGCCCCUAAUAAGGCUAGAGGUCUAAGUCCCCCACCCCUUUCCCCACUCCCCUCUAGUGGUGAACUUUAGAGGAAAAGGAAGUAAUUGCACAAGGAGUUUGAUUCUUACCUUUUCUCAGUUACAGAGGACAUUAACUGGAUCAUUGCUUCCCCAGGGCAGGAGAGCGCAGAGCUAGGGAAAGUGAAAGGUAAUGAAGAUGGAGCAGAAUGAGCAGAUGCAGAUCACCAGCAAAGUGCACUGAUGUGUGAGCUCUUAAGACCACUCAGCAUGACGACUGAGUAGACUUGUUUACAUCUGAUCAAAGCACUGGGCUUGUCCAGGCUCAUAAUAAAUGCUCCAUUGAAUCUACUAUUCUUGUUUUCCACUGCUGUGGAAACCUCCUUGCUACUAUAGCGUCUUAUGUAUGGUUUAAAGGAAAUUUAUCAGGUGAGAGAGAUGAGCAACGUUGUCUUUUCUCUCAAAGCUGUAAUGUGGGUUUUGUUUUAUUGUUUAUUUGUUUGUUGUUGUAUCCUUUUCUCCUUGUUAUUUGCCCUUCAGAAUGCACUUGGGAAAGGCUGGUUCCUUAGCCUCCUGGUUUGUGUCUUUUUUUUUUUUUUUUUAAAACAGAAUCACUCUGGCAAUUGUCUGCAGCUGCCACUGGUGCAAGGCCUUACCAGCCCUAGCCUCUAGCACUUCUCUAAGUGCCAAAAACAGUGUCAUUGUGUGUGUUCCUUUCUUGAUACUUAGUCAUGGGAGGAUAUUACAAAAAAGAAAUUUAAAUUGUGUUCAUAGUCUUUCAGAGUAGCUCACUUUAGUCCUGUAACUUUAUUGGGUGAUAUUUUGUGUUCAGUGUAAUUGUCUUCUCUUUGCUGAUUAUGUUACCAUGGUACUCCUAAAGCAUAUGCCUCACCUGGUUAAAAAAGAACAAACAUGUUUUUGUGAAAGCUACUGAAGUGCCUUGGGAAAUGAGAAAGUUUUAAUAAGUAAAAUGAUUUUUUAAAUAA